GGGAGUCUGGUUAGUACAAGGGGAAGCCUAGUGGGUCUGGCGCUCCGUUUUCAAGACACUCGGAGUCCGUCUUUGAGGGGAAAGGUCAUGGCCCUGAAACCACCUUCUGCCACCCAGCCUGCUCCCAACGCGCCAGCUACCCCAGACGCCCCCCCUACCACAGGUGAUCCAGGUGCUUCAGCUGCCCCAGGUUCUCCCACUACCACAGGUGGUCCAGGUGCCCCAGCUGAGGUGCCCCAGGAGCCGCAAGAGCCUACACAGACACCAGAGGAACUAGCAUUUUACGCCCCAAACUACCUAUGUUUGACCAUCUUUGCUAUACUUUUAUUCCCUCCAUUUGGAUUGGCAGCUUUGUACUUCUCUUAUGAGGGUUCCUGGACACAGAAACCCACAUCUAUGCUUCCACCCCUACAGACUAUGAAGGCCAACCAGAACAGUGAAUGGGAAGAGGCUUACAUCAACUCAGGCCGAACUGGUUGGUUCGGUGCAUUCGUGGUAAUGAUUGGCUUAGGCAUCAUUUAUGGCUUGGUCCUAUAUUAAUGAAGUCUAGGCAUAGCAACCCAGGGGUCCGCUCCCCAACCGAGCCACUCACCAAACACUAACCAGCCAAGUCAGCCAUCAGGCAAGAAAUUCAACCGCUGAGACAUCUAGCCAAGAAAUCCUCUAACCAAGGAACUCAACAUUCAAGAA